GUCCCCGCCGCCCCGACGCUUCCGCCCGGUCCGUCGGCACGUCGGCCCUGCCUCCCGGACCACCCUGCGGGGCGCACCAGCGAUCUGGGGUGCGGGGCUCGGCCUCCCUGCGCUCCUGGCUGACCGUGUGACCUUGGGUCUUAACCAUGAACUUCUCUGGAGGAGGGAGGCAGGAAGCAGCAGGGUCCAGGGGUAGAAGGGCUCCCAGACCCCGAGAACAGGACCGAGACGUGCAGCUGUCCAAGGCUCUGUCCUAUGCCCUGCGCCAUGGGGCCUUGAAGCUGGGGCUUCCCAUGGGAGCUGAUGGCUUCGUGCCCCUGGGCACCCUCCUGCAGUUGCCCCAGUUCCGCGGCUUCUCUGCUGAAGAUGUGCAGCGCGUGGUGGACACCAAUAGGAAGCAGCGGUUCGCCCUGCAGCUGGGGGAUCCCAGCACUGGCCUUCUCAUCCGGGCCAACCAGGGCCAUUCCCUGCAGGUACCUAAGUUGGAGCUGAUGCCCCUGGAGACACCGCAGGCCCUGCCCCCGAUGCUAGUCCAUGGUACAUUCUGGAAGCACUGGCCAUCCAUCCUACUCAAAGGCCUGUCCUGCCAGGGAAGGACGCACAUUCACCUGGCCCCAGGACUGCCUGGAGACCCCGGUAUCAUCAGUGGCAUGCGGUCCCAUUGUGAAAUAGCUGUGUUCAUCGAUGGACCCCUGGCUCUGGCAGCAGAUGGAAUACCCUUCUUCCGCUCUGCCAAUGGGGUGAUUCUGACUCCAGGGAAUACUGAUGGCUUCCUCCUUCCCAAGUACUUCAAGGAGGCCCUGCAGCUACGCCCUACCCGAAAGCCCCUUUCCUUGGCUGGUGAUGAAGAGACAGAGUGUCAGAGUAGCCCCAAGCACAGCUCCAGAGAAAGGAGGAGGAUCCAACAAUAAAAUAUUAAUUUAUAAAAAAGAAAUUUUAAAAAGUAACAAGAAAGAACUCGUUUGAAACCAUGUUUCAUCAUCCUGUA